GAGACUUGAGCGUGACUGCGGAGCCUGGAGGAUGCGGGCUCCCCGAGCGGGCUUCCCCUCUGCCCGGCGCGAUGGAGCGGGUCGGUGAGCGGAACAAAGGCGCCUGCCCGGGGGAGCGGGUCUUCCGCUGAAGAGCGCGGGUGGCGCGCCGCGACGGCCGCCUGCGGGCCAAGGUGGGAGGCUGUGCGGCCCCAGGCGCGGCGCGCUCCGCCGUGGGCGGGCGGCGAUCCCUGAGUCCGGCACCUGUGCGCCGCUCCCUCUGUGCCUCCCGGGCAGCCCCGCCUGCCGGCCUCGGAGUCCGCGGCGCCGGCGGCUAGAGGUCCAGAGGCGAACCACUUGCUGGUGCAGAAGAGAAACCCUCAAAUCCCUGGCCUUUCGCGGAGACGCCUGGACGGGGCCGUGCGCCGUGGACUGAGCAGGCGUCUCGGGGAGCACUUCUGCAGAGCGAGGACUUCCAUGUGAGCGAUUCCGUUCUCCCCACCACCAAUCCGACCUCCCAGCCGUCUCCGCCGCCCGAGCAUCCUUGAGGUGGGACGAGCAGGGGCUUGGAUCCCUGCCGGCCGUCUGGUGUGUGAGGCUUGCACGGCCCCUGGCUGCCCCGCGCCUCGCCGGAGCCCGAGGGGGCGCAGGUCCGGGGCGAGGGCCGGCCGGGCUGUUUGAUGGCUUCACUGAGAAGAGUCAAAGUGCUGUUGGUGUUGAACUUGAUCGCGGUAGCCGGCUUCGUGCUCUUCCUGGCCAAGUGCCGGCCCAUCGCGGUGCGCAGCGGAGACGCCUUCCACGAGAUCCGGCCGCGCGCCGAGGUGGCCAACCUCAGCGCGCACAGCGCCAGCCCCAUCCAGGAUGCGGUCCUGAAGCGCCUGUCGCUGCUGGAGGACAUCGUGUACCGGCAGCUGAAUGGCUUAUCCAAAUCCCUUGGGCUCAUUGAAGGUUAUGGUGGGCGGGGUAAAGGGGGCCUUCCGGCUACUCUUUCCCCGGCUGAAGAAGAAAAGGCUAAGGGACCCCAUGAGAAGUAUGGCUACAAUUCAUACCUCAGUGAAAAAAUUUCACUGGACCGUUCCAUUCCGGAUUAUCGUCCCACCAAGUGUAAGGAGCUCAAGUACUCCAAGGACCUGCCCCAGAUAUCCAUCAUAUUCAUCUUCGUGAACGAGGCCCUGUCGGUGAUCCUGCGGUCCGUGCACAGUGCCGUCAAUCACACGCCCACACACCUGCUGAAGGAAAUCAUUCUGGUGGAUGACAACAGCGACGAAGAGGAGCUGAAGGUCCCCCUAGAGGAGUAUGUCCACAAACGCUACCCCGGGCUGGUGAAGGUGGUAAGAAAUCAGAAGAGGGAAGGCCUGAUCCGCGCUCGCAUUGAGGGCUGGAAGGUGGCUACCGGGCAGGUCACUGGCUUCUUUGAUGCCCACGUGGAAUUCACCGCUGGCUGGGCUGAGCCGGUUCUAUCCCGCAUCCAGGAAAACCGGAAGCGUGUGAUCCUCCCCUCCAUUGACAACAUCAAACAGGACAACUUUGAGGUGCAGCGGUACGAGAACUCGGCCCACGGGUACAGCUGGGAGCUGUGGUGCAUGUACAUCAGCCCCCCAAAAGACUGGUGGGACGCCGGAGACCCUUCUCUCCCCAUCAGGACCCCAGCCAUGAUAGGCUGCUCGUUCGUGGUCAACAGGAAGUUCUUCGGUGAAAUUGGUCUUCUGGAUCCUGGCAUGGAUGUAUACGGAGGAGAAAAUAUUGAACUGGGAAUCAAGAGAUGGGGGUCUCACUAUGUUGCCCAGGCUGAUGUCAAACUCCUGACCUCAAGGGACUGUUCCAUCUCAGCCUCUCAACAUGCUGGGACCACAGCCGUGAGCCACUGUGCCUGGCCUUAUAUAGAAAUUAUGAGCCAUCUGGAAUAGCCAAAGCCCCAGGAACCUGAAUGAAAACAGCAUUUCCCACUCCCACAGGUCUCUUUGCCCUGUCUCUUGUUCUUAGUUUUGCUUCCCUCUUGUCUACAGCUAGCUCUUGCAAGGCCUUCUGCCUGCCCUCCUGAUCCCCGCCCUAGCCACUUCUCUAUGGUUUUAGGGACCCAUCCAUCCAUGUUAACCAAGAGAGAUUUCCCCCUGCCUUCUCUGAGACCUCUGGCAUCAGGAACCCUGAUGUCCCAAAGCCUUCUGUGGCCUGUGUUGUCCAUUUGGAACUCUCGAGCUCAAAUUUGCUACAUCCAUUGAAUAAUGUAAUUUGCAUCAUGGUCCAUCCCAGAGAGGACCAGAUGAUCAGUCCGUUUUCAUUUUCAUACUUUUUAGAUUGCAUGAGUCUUUGUUCUCUCACCUAUUGGCACUGGUCAAGGUUGGAUCCAAGGCCUGGUGUGAAGGAAGUCAUCCUUGGCUAUGUGAAUACCUUUGUAGGGCAGAGCCCAAGUUUAUCUGUGAUACAGAUCAAAGCAAAGUUCCUGGUCUUGUCCCAGUAUAGAGUGAGCCUUGAGAUUUCACAAACUGGUCUUUCAUGGAGGGGAAUGUAUGACUGGUGGCCAACAGUUCAACUGAAUACUUCUGAUUAAAUGGAAACUUGGUGAGUGCCUUCUGUAGCCCAGCAGGCAUUUCCACUGGAGCUACCACAGUCAAUACAUGGGGUCUCUAUCUCCAUGAAAUUUAUAGUCAGACAGAAAUACUGUUCAUGAAAUAAAUAAUUAGCACUGUGAUGAGUGUGAAAAAACAAGAUAGAGCAAUGCUGUGGGAAAAUAUAGUAAGGAAAUAUAGCCUAGUCUAGGGAGUUGGGAGGAACCUUCUUACGGAAAUGCUGUUUAAGAAUUCUAAAGUGAGUUUAAUAUAGAUAAGCAAAGAAGGAGGUGUGCAAGGAAGAAUAUUCUAGACAGAAAAACAUCUGCAAAGAUUUGGAAUUCUGAGAGAUAAAUGUGUCCUGAGGACCUUGGGAGUUCAGGAUGGUUAGAGCAGAGAAAGGGGGAAGAAAACCUCUUAGAUGCAGCGACAACCAUCAAGGUGGGGCCCAGAUUAUGAGGAUUGAUAAGCAGAAAGUUGGCUUUUUCUUAAGGAUCACUGUAGACAUUUUAGAUAGGUAGGUUAGGUAGACAAAUAGAUAGGUAGGUAGGAAGAAAGAGAGAGAGAGGGAGAGACAGAGACAUGAUAGAUACAUAGAUUAGAGAGAGAAAGAUGCAUGGAUGAUGGAUGGAUGGAUGGAUAGAUAGAGGGAUGAUAGAGAUAGAUGAUAGAUUAAUGAUAGAGAUAGUAGGUAAUAGAGAUAUAGACGAUAGAGAUGAUGGAUGGAUAGAUAGAGAUGAUGGAUAGAAUGAUAGAUUAGAUAGAUGAAAUAUAUAGGUAUGGAUAGAUUGAUAGAUUAUAGAUUAGAUUGAUAAUAGAGAUAACAGAUAGAUGGAUAGAUGAUAUAGAUAGAUGAGAUAUAGGUUAGAUAGAGAUGAUGGAUUCGAUAGAUGAUUGAUGGAUAGAUAGAGAUGAUAGACUGAUUAUAUAGACAGAUAAAUAGAUGAUAGUUUGAUAGAUUAGAUAGAUGAUAGAUAAGAUACAUGGAUGAUAGAUGUAGAUGAUAGAUGGAUACAAAGAAGAUAGAUAUAGAUGAUAGAUUAGACAGAUGAUAUAUAAAUAGAUGAUAGAUAAAUUGAUAGAUGGAUGAUAGAUAGAUAGAUAGAUAGAUAGAUAGAUAGAUAGAUAGAUAGAUGAGACAUAGAUAGUCUCAAGUACCCAUUACUUACCACCCUUGAGGGGAUUUAAAAGAAGUAAGAGGAUUAGACUUUUCUUUUUACUAAAAAGAUAAUGAUGACAGCCAUGUGGAAAAUAGAUGAUAAAGCUGCGUACACUCAGGAAAAGCUGGUGAGGAGGGGCUUGACCUAUAUGGUUGUGACAGUGGGAGAGGAAUGGACAAAUUCAGGAAGUGGAAGAGACAAGGCCUGGAGAUUGAGUGUAUGCAGGGGAUGAAGAGAAGUGGGAGUCCAGGCUGAGCAGGUGGGAAAUAGUGUUGCUGUUCUCUAAGGAGCACUGUUGGAGGAGGUUUGGGAGAAGGUGGAAAGAUUAUAUGAUAAAUCUCAUGUUUCUGAGACACCCCAGGCCAGCCCAGAGGCAUUUGCAUGUGUGGGGAUUAAGCCAAGGAGGGAGCACUAAGCCUGAGAUAGACUUGGAUGUACCGGUGCCCUUUAGGAGGUGUGAUAGACAGAGAGUGGUUGUAUUAAUCUGUUCUUACACUGCUAUAAAGACAUACCUGAGACUGGGUAAUUUAUAAACAAAAGACAGUUAAUUGAUUCACAGUUGUGCAUGGCUGGGGAGGCCUCAGGAAACGUACAAUCAUGGUGGAAGGGGAAGGAGAAUCAAGGCAUGUUUUAGCUGGUGGCAGGAGAGAGACCAAGCAAGGGAGGAAGGGCUAAACACUUUUAUGUUUUGUUUUGUUUUGAUUGAGACAUAGUCUCUCGCCCUGUCACCCAGGCUGGAGUACAGUGGCUCAAUCUCAGCUCACUAUAACCUCCAUCUCCUGGGCUCAAGUGAUUCUCAUGCCUCAGCCUCCCAAGUAGCUGGGAUUACAGAUGUGCACUACCAUGCUCGGCUAAUUUUUGUAUUUUUAGUAGAGAUGAGGUUUCACCAUGAUGGCCAGGCUGGUCUUGAACUCCUGGCCUCAUGUGAUCCACCCGCCUUGGCCUCCCAAAGUGCUAGGAUUACAGCUGUGAGCCACUGCGCCCGGCCACGUUUAAAGCAUCAGAUCUCGUGAGAACUCACUCACUAUCAUAAGAACAGCAUGGGGGAAACCAACCCCCAUGAUCCAAUCACCUCUUACCAGGUCCCUCCUUCAACGCGUGGGGAUUACAAUUUGGAUUACAAUUCACGAUGGGAUUUGGGUGGGGAGACAGAGGCAAAUUAUAUCAGUGGUGGUCCACUGAAUGAGAGGAGUGAAUGAGAAGGGAUUAUUAAGGGUAUCUCCCAGGCUUCCCAGCAACUGACUGCAAUCCCCUAAAUAGAGGACUCUGGUAGGGUAGGUUUGUCAGUGGGGACAUGAGUAGUUCCAUUUUAGAAAUGCUGAGUUUGAGGAGUAGCAGUUCUCUCUAACCUGACAGUGAGAUGUCAAGGGAACACAAGGCUGGGAAGGGACUCUGGCCAAGAGUGGGAUUUGGCAGAGGGGUGCCAGGACAAGAGUUGGCUAUUCUCCAUUCCACCCUGGAGUCUGCAAGGCCACAGUGCUUAGGGUGUGGGCUGACUUAGAGGAGCGAGGACAUAGGGAUUCCUGCUAUGGUUUGAGCGUGUGAGUUACAGCAGGUAGUGGCCAUAUGUGUUAUACCUGGUGGGAAUGUAAACUAGAACAAUCACUAUGAAAAACAGUAUGGAGAUUCCUUAAAUAACUAAAAGUAGAACUACGAUUUGAUCCAGCAGUCCCACUACUGUUAUCUACCCAGAGGAAAAGAAGUCAUUUUACAAAAAAGAUACUUGCACACACAUGUUUGUAGCAGCACAAUUCGUAAUUGCAAAAAUGUGGAACCAACCCAAAUGCCCAUCAAUCAAAGAGUGGAUGGAGAAUCUGUGGUGGCCGGGUGCAGUGCCUCACACCUGUAAUCGCAGCACUUUGGGAGGUCAAGACGGGCAGAUCACGAGAUCAGGAGAUGGAGAUCAUCCUGGCCAACAUGGUGAAACACUGUCUCUAUUAAAAAUACAAAAAAAAAAAAAAAUAGCUGGGCAUGGUGACAUGCGCCUUAGACCCAGCUACUCGGGAGGCUGAGGAAGGGGAAUCUCUUGAACCUGGGAGGCGGAGGUUGCAGUGAGCUGAGAUCGUGCCACUGCACUCCAGCCUGGUGACAGAGCAAGACUCCGUCUC